AUAUUGGAAUACUCUGUUGACAAGUAGAUACCACUUCACCUCUGCUAGGGUGAGCGCUGGUAGCUCCUCCCUGUUAAAUGCCCAUCUCAAUGCCUCUGCCCUAAGUGAGUUGUGCAAUAAAUGAGCUGUCACUCUGAACAGGUGGGAAAGAAGUGAACUGCUUGUUCACUUGCUGCUGUUGCCACUGCUGGUACAGAAAUAGAAGCACAAAAAAACAAAGACAAAAAACCUCCAAGCUCCCUUCAGUAGUUGCUACACCUUCAGAUUGAGACAUCCUUCCUCAUUUACAAACCUCAGCUGUGUCUGGGGGCAGGGCCACAGUGAAACUGCCAGGAGCAAAAAGGCUUCCAAGAAAAAGUACCACAUCAGAUUGGAAACUGGGGACAGAUCAUUCCUGGGAUGUGACGGGCACCAGAAUGCUCCCUCUCCAAAGGAUCUAAGGACCAAAGCUGACAGUUUCUUUACUUGUGCUGAAGAAUCAGGAGACAAACUUGAAUUUGUAAUAUUAAGAAAAAGAAAAAAAAGGAGAAAACCCACACCCAUCACUGAAGUAAUUUCAAAAACAAGCAAUUUACUUGUGCCCAACAGAAGUCCCAGACAAACUUCUAUUACUCUGAAGAGAAAAAAUAUGGUAGCUGACAGCAUCUACUCCUGAAGACCGGAAACAUGGCUUGUACCAUCCAAAAGGCAGAAGCACUUGACGGGGCUCAUUUGAUGCAGAUCCUCUGGUAUGAUGAGGAAGAGUCUCUCUACCCAGCUGUAUGGUUGAGAGACAACUGUCCGUGCUCUGAUUGCUACCUGGAUUCUGCAAAAGCACGGAAACUUCUAGUGGAAGCUCUUGAUGUGAACAUUGGAAUUAAAGGCUUGAUAUUUGACAGAAAAAAGGUGUACAUCACAUGGCCCGAUGAGCAUUACAGUGAAUUCCAGGCUGAUUGGCUGAAGAAAAGAUGCUUUUCCAAGCAGGCCAGAGCAAAGCUCCAAAGAGAAUUGUUUUUUCCAGAAUGCCAAUACUGGGGCUCAGAGCUCCAGCUACCCACUUUGGAUUUUGAAGAUGUUUUAAGAUAUGAUGAACACGCAUACAAGUGGCUCUCCACCCUCAAGAAAGUAGGCAUAGUAAGACUCACCGGAGCAUCUGACAAACCAGGAGAAGUUUCAAAACUUGGGAAAAGGAUGGGUUUCCUCUAUCUCACAUUUUAUGGACAUACUUGGCAAGUGCAAGACAAAAUCGAUGCAAACAAUGUGGCUUACACAACUGGGAAGCUAAGCUUUCACACUGAUUAUCCAGCCCUCCAUCAUCCACCUGGGGUUCAGCUUCUUCACUGCAUAAAGCAAACAGUCACAGGGGGUGAUUCAGAAAUUGUAGAUGGGUUUAAUGUGUGCCAAAAACUAAAGAAAAAUAAUCCUCAGGCAUUCCAGAUUUUGUCCUCUACCUUUGUGGACUUUACAGACAUUGGAGUGGAUUACUGUGAUUUUUCUGUACAAUCAAAACAUAAAAUUAUAGAGUUAGAUGAUAAAGGCCAAGUGGUUCGCAUCAACUUCAAUAACGCAACUAGGGACACAAUAUUUGAUGUGCCUGUUGAAAGAGUUCAGCCUUUUUAUGCUGCUCUGAAGGAGUUUGUUGACCUCAUGAACAGCAAAGAAUCCAAGUUUACCUUCAAGAUGAAUCCAGGUGAUGUGAUUACUUUUGAUAACUGGCGCUUACUUCAUGGCCGACGUAGCUAUGAAGCAGGAACUGAGAUAUCCCGCCAUCUAGAAGGAGCUUAUGCUGACUGGGAUGUGGUCAUGUCAAGGCUUCGUAUCUUAAGGCAGAGGGUGGAGAAUGGAAACUGAAGUCACCUGUAGAUAAUUUUAAUAAGAUUCCAAUGACCAUAUUUUGUGAGAUAUGGCACAUUAUUCACAGACCAUGAUCUUUGUGAUUUACAUAUAAUUUCCUUAACAAUGAACAUGUAACUUCUCUCACAAGAGUACUCUUUACUUUGUAAUCAUAUACAAUGUCAACUUUUUAGAUGUUUCACCACUCUUUUGCAAAUAAAGCAUCCUUUCUGCUCUGUUGCAUGCCUGCUCUAAUUUCUUUUGCCCAUAUAUGAGUAUCUCCAGAAUGUCUACAAAUAGUUUUUGUAGCAAAUGAAAAUUUCUUCAAAUAAGCCUUUUGUUUCAAAUAAAACUUGUCUCAAAACAUGCUUCUA